GUCGCUCGCGCUGGAAGAAGCGGAAGAAGAUGGCGCUCACCAGCUUUUUACCUGCACCUACUCAGCUAUCUCAGGACCAGCUUGAGGCUGAAGAAAAGGCAAGAUCCCAGAGAUCACGGCAGACCUCACUGGUCUCCUCCCGAAGAGAACCUCCCCCGUACGGAUACCGGAAAGGCUGGAUACCUCGGUUAUUAGAGGAUUUUGGAGAUGGAGGUGCUUUUCCAGAGAUCCAUGUGGCCCAGUAUCCACUGGAUAUGGGACGAAAGAAAAAAAUGUCGAAUGCGCUGGCCAUUCAGGUGGAUUCUGAAGGAAAAAUUAAAUAUGAUGCAAUUGCUCGACAAGGACAGUCAAAAGACAAGGUCAUUUAUAGCAAAUACACUGACCUGGUUCCAAAGGAGGUUAUGAAUGCAGAUGAUCCAGACCUGCAAAGGCCCGAUGAAGAAGCUAUUAAAGAGAUAACAGAAAAGACAAGAGUAGCCUUAGAAAAAUCUGUAUCACAGAAGGUCGCCGCAGCCAUGCCAGUUCGAGCAGCUGACAAAUUGGCUCCUGCUCAGUAUAUCCGAUACACACCAUCUCAGCAAGGAGUGGCAUUCAACUCUGGAGCUAAACAGAGGGUUAUUCGGAUGGUAGAAAUGCAGAAAGAUCCAAUGGAGCCUCCAAGGUUCAAGAUUAAUAAGAAAAUUCCCCGGGGACCACCUUCUCCUCCUGCGCCUGUCAUGCAUUCUCCUAGCCGAAAGAUGACUGUAAAGGAACAACAAGAGUGGAAGAUUCCUCCUUGUAUUUCUAACUGGAAAAAUGCAAAGGGUUAUACAAUUCCAUUAGACAAACGUCUGGCUGCUGAUGGAAGAGGACUACAGACAGUACACAUAAAUGAAAAUUUCGCCAAAUUGGCAGAAGCCCUCUACAUUGCUGAUCGGAAGGCUCGUGAAGCUGUGGAAAUGCGUGCCCAAGUAGAGAGAAAAAUGGCUCAGAAAGAAAAGGAAAAACAUGAAGAGAAACUUAGAGAAAUGGCCCAGAAAGCCAGGGAGAGAAGAGCUGGGAUCAAAACUCAUGUGGAAAAAGAGGAUGGGGAGGCACGUGAGAGGGAUGAAAUCCGGCAUGACAGGCGAAAAGAGAGACAGCAUGACCGGAAUCUUUCCAGGGCAGCUCCUGAUAAGAGGUCGAAACUUCAGAGAAAUGAAAAUCGGGAUAUCAGUGAAGUUAUUGCUCUCGGUGUUCCUAAUCCUCGGACUUCCAAUGAAGUUCAGUAUGACCAAAGGCUCUUCAACCAAUCCAAGGGUAUGGACAGUGGAUUUGCAGGUGGAGAAGAUGAAAUUUAUAAUGUUUAUGAUCAAGCCUGGAGAGGUGGUAAAGAUAUGGCCCAGAGUAUUUAUAGGCCCAGUAAAAAUCUGGACAAGGACAUGUAUGGUGAUGACCUAGAAGCCAGAAUAAAGACCAACAGGUGCCAAGCCAUACAACUCAAUUUCAGUGUUUACACUGGUGAAAGCAAAGUAGUUCAUAGUUUUUUCUCCUUUUCCUUAGAUUUGUUCCCGACAAGGAGUUUUCUGGUUCAGACCGUAGACAGAGAGGCCGAGAAGGACCAGUGCAGUUUGAGGAAGAUCCUUUUGGUUUGGACAAGUUUUUGGAAGAAGCCAAACAGCAUGGUGGCUCUAAAAGACCCUCAGAUAGCAGCCGCCCCAAGGAACACGAGCAUGAAGGCAAGAAGAGGAGGAAGGAAUAGGCACAGGUCUCUCCAAAGUGAAUGAACUCUUACCCAUAACCCUAAUGAUGCAAGUCAUAUGGGGGAACACUUUGUAAAUGGUCAGGAUAAAAACCAAAUCUGGGUGCCAGAUCCCAGCACUACUUUUUAUUACUGGAGAAAUGGGGGGGAUAGAAAAUUCUACUUUGAAUUAUUUAGUUUUUUUUAAAGAGUGGGUUGUGUUUGUGCUUCUCCCACCUUUCAGCAUUUAUAGAACAUGCUGCCCCACAUACAAAGUCAAGACCACUUACUUUUAUGUGACACUAGUAGUUUGGGGUUAAUGUUUUGUGUAAGAACAGCUGCAUAUGAGUAAAGUUACCCCAACCACAGUGAGGAGGAAGAUGUUCACAUACUGGAACUGUCCUGCCAAAUAAAUUUUGCCCCUAUUGUGCUCUGUUUUAAUUUGGAGUGGGCAAAGUAACCUCUUGCUUGGUGCAACUAUUUGUUUCAAAUAAAAACAUUUAGACAAAA